CCCGGCUUGGGAGCCGGAGGUCAGCGGCUGCGCGGCCGGCCCCCUCCCACGGGAGCCGCGCCAGGGCCCAGCAAGAGUCGGGCGGGAUCGCUAUUGUUUUUGGCGAGCACAUAAAUCCCCGGGCCGACCCACUGCGCACCCAGGUUUCCUCCCGGAGGCCUUUCGGUUUCCUCUGAGGCCCUAUAUAGAGGCUCCAGGCCCGGACUGUGCAGAGGAGGGAGGCGCCCUGGAGUCUCCCCUCCAGCGAGAGGGGCUGCGCGGGCCGGGCCGGGCCGGGCUGGGCUGGAGCAGCGGCGGCCGCGGGAGCCGAGCUUGCAGCGAGGGACCGGCUGAGGCGCGCGGGAGGGAAGGAGGCAAGGGCUCCGCGGCGCUGUCGCCGCCGCUGCCGCUCACUCUCGGGGAAGAGAUGGCGGCGGAGCGGGGAGCCCGGCGACUCCUCAGCACCCCCUCCUUCUGGCUCUACUGCCUGCUGCUGCUCGGGCGCCGGGCGCCGGGCGCCGCGGCCGCCAGGAGCGGCUCCGCGCCGCAGUCCCCAGGAGCCAGCAUUCGAACGUUCACUCCAUUUUAUUUUCUGGUGGAGCCGGUGGAUACACUCUCAGUUAGAGGCUCUUCUGUUAUAUUAAACUGUUCAGCAUAUUCUGAGCCUUCUCCAAAAAUUGAAUGGAAAAAAGAUGGAACUUUUUUAAACUUAGUAUCAGAUGAUCGACGCCAGCUUCUCCCGGAUGGAUCUUUAUUUAUCAGCAAUGUGGUGCAUUCCAAACACAAUAAACCUGAUGAAGGUUAUUAUCAGUGUGUGGCCACUGUUGAGAGUCUUGGAACUAUUAUCAGUAGAACAGCGAAGCUCAUAGUAGCAGGUCUUCCAAGAUUUACCAGCCAACCAGAACCUUCCUCAGUUUAUGCUGGGAACAAUGCAAUUCUGAAUUGUGAAGUUAAUGCAGAUUUGGUCCCAUUUGUGAGGUGGGAACAGAACAGACAACCCCUUCUUCUGGAUGAUAGAGUUAUCAAACUUCCAAGUGGAAUGCUGGUUAUCAGCAAUGCAACUGAAGGAGAUGGCGGGCUUUAUCGCUGCGUAGUGGAAAGUGGUGGGCCACCAAAGUAUAGUGAUGAAGUUGAAUUGAAGGUUCUUCCAGAUCCUGAGGUGAUAUCAGACUUGGUAUUUUUGAAACAGCCUUCUCCCUUAGUCAGAGUCAUUGGUCAGGAUGUAGUGUUGCCAUGUGUUGCUUCAGGACUUCCUACUCCAACCAUUAAAUGGAUGAAAAAUGAGGAGGCACUUGACACAGAAAGCUCUGAAAGAUUGGUAUUGCUGGCAGGUGGUAGCCUGGAGAUCAGUGAUGUUACUGAGGAUGAUGCUGGGACUUAUUUUUGUAUAGCUGAUAAUGGAAAUGAGACAAUUGAAGCUCAAGCAGAGCUUACAGUGCAAGCUCAACCUGAAUUCCUGAAGCAGCCUACUAAUAUAUAUGCUCACGAAUCUAUGGAUAUUGUAUUUGAAUGUGAAGUGACUGGAAAACCAACUCCAACUGUGAAGUGGGUCAAAAAUGGGGAUAUGGUUAUCCCAAGUGAUUAUUUUAAGAUUGUAAAGGAACAUAAUCUUCAAGUUUUGGGUCUGGUGAAAUCAGAUGAAGGGUUCUAUCAGUGCAUUGCUGAAAAUGAUGUUGGAAAUGCACAAGCUGGAGCCCAACUGAUAAUCCUUGAACAUGAUGUUGCCAUCCCAACAUUACCUCCCACUUCACUGACCAGUGCCACUACUGACCAUCUAGCACCAGCCACAACGGGACCACUGCCUUCAGCUCCUCGGGAUGUCGUGGCCUCCCUGGUCUCUACCCGCUUCAUCAAAUUGACGUGGCGGACACCUGCAUCAGAUCCUCACGGAGACAACCUUACCUACUCUGUGUUCUACACCAAGGAAGGGAUUGCUAGGGAACGUGUUGAGAAUACCAGUCACCCAGGAGAGAUGCAAGUAACCAUUCAAAACCUAAUGCCAGCGACCGUGUACAUCUUUAGAGUUAUGGCUCAAAAUAAGCAUGGCUCAGGAGAGAGUUCAGCUCCACUGCGAGUAGAAACACAACCUGAGGUUCAGCUCCCUGGCCCAGCACCUAACCUUCGUGCAUAUGCAGCUUCGCCUACCUCCAUCACUGUUACGUGGGAAACACCAGUGUCUGGCAAUGGGGAAAUUCAGAAUUAUAAAUUGUACUACAUGGAAAAGGGGACUGAUAAAGAACAGGAUGUUGAUGUUUCAAGUCACUCUUACACCAUUAAUGGGUUGAAAAAAUAUACAGAGUAUAGUUUCCGAGUGGUGGCCUACAAUAAACAUGGUCCUGGAGUUUCCACACCAGAUGUUGCUGUUCGAACAUUGUCAGAUGUUCCCAGUGCUGCUCCUCAGAAUCUGUCCUUGGAAGUGAGAAAUUCAAAGAGUAUUAUGAUUCACUGGCAGCCACCUGCUCCAGCCACACAAAAUGGGCAGAUUACUGGCUACAAGAUUCGCUACCGAAAGGCCUCCCGAAAGAGUGAUGUCACUGAGACCUUGGUAAGCGGGACACAGCUGUCUCAGCUGAUUGAAGGUCUUGAUCGGGGGACUGAGUAUAAUUUCCGAGUGGCUGCUCUAACAAUCAAUGGUACAGGCCCGGCAACUGACUGGCUGUCUGCUGAAACUUUUGAAAGUGACCUAGAUGAAACUCGUGUUCCUGAAGUGCCUAGCUCUCUUCACGUACGCCCGCUCGUUACUAGCAUCGUAGUGAGCUGGACUCCUCCAGAGAAUCAGAACAUUGUGGUCAGAGGUUACGCCAUUGGUUAUGGCAUUGGCAGCCCUCAUGCCCAGACCAUCAAAGUGGACUAUAAACAGCGCUAUUACACCAUUGAAAAUCUGGAUCCCAGCUCUCACUAUGUGAUUACCCUGAAAGCAUUUAAUAACGUGGGUGAAGGCAUCCCCCUGUAUGAGAGUGCUGUGACCAGGCCUCACACAGUGCCAGAUCCCACUCCCAUGAUGCCACCAGUGGGAGUUCAGGCUUCCAUUCUGAGUCAUGACACCAUCAGGAUUACGUGGGCAGACAACUCGCUGCCCAAGCACCAGAAGAUUACAGACUCCCGAUACUACACCGUCCGAUGGAAAACCAACAUCCCAGCAAACACCAAGUACAAGAAUGCAAAUGCAACCACUUUGAGUUAUUUGGUGACUGGUUUAAAGCCGAAUACACUCUAUGAAUUCUCUGUGAUGGUGACCAAAGGUCGAAGAUCAAGUACAUGGAGUAUGACAGCCCAUGGGACCACCUUUGAAUUAGUUCCGACUUCUCCACCCAAGGAUGUGACUGUUGUGAGUAAAGAGGGGAAACCUAAGACCAUAAUUGUGAAUUGGCAGCCUCCCUCCGAAGCCAAUGGCAAAAUUACAGGUUACAUCAUAUAUUACAGUACAGAUGUGAAUGCAGAGAUACAUGACUGGGUUAUUGAGCCUGUUGUGGGAAACAGACUGACUCACCAGAUACAAGAGUUAACUCUUGACACACCAUACUACUUCAAAAUCCAGGCACGGAACUCAAAGGGCAUGGGACCCAUGUCUGAAGCUGUCCAAUUCAGAACACCUAAAGCCUCAGGGUCUGGAGGGAAAGGAAGCCGGCUGCCAGACCUAGGAUCCGACUACAAACCUCCAAUGAGCGGCAGUAACAGCCCUCAUGGGAGCCCCACCUCUCCUCUGGACAGUAAUAUGCUGCUGGUCAUAAUUGUUUCUGUUGGCGUCAUCACCAUCGUGGUGGUUGUGAUUAUCGCUGUCUUUUGUACCCGUCGUACCACCUCUCACCAGAAAAAGAAACGAGCUGCCUGCAAAUCAGUGAAUGGCUCUCAUAAGUACAAAGGGAAUUCCAAAGAUGUGAAACCUCCAGAUCUCUGGAUCCAUCAUGAGAGACUGGAGCUGAAACCCAUUGAUAAGUCUCCAGACCCAAACCCCAUCAUGACUGAUACUCCAAUUCCUCGCAACUCUCAAGAUAUCACACCAGUUGACAACUCCAUGGACAGCAAUAUCCAUCAAAGGCGAAAUUCAUACAGAGGGCAUGAGUCAGAGGACAGCAUGUCUACACUGGCUGGAAGGCGAGGAAUGAGACCAAAAAUGAUGAUGCCCUUUGACUCCCAGCCACCCCAGCCUGUGAUUAGUGCCCAUCCCAUCCAUUCCCUCGAUAACCCUCACCAUCAUUUCCACUCCAGCAGCCUCGCUUCUCCAGCUCGCAGUCAUCUCUACCACCCGGGCAGCCCAUGGCCCAUUGGCACAUCCAUGUCCCUUUCAGACAGGGCCAAUUCCACAGAAUCCGUUCGAAAUACCCCCAGCACUGACACCAUGCCAGCCUCUUCGUCUCAAACAUGCUGCACUGAUCACCAGGACCCUGAAGGUGCUACCAGCUCCUCUUACUUGGCCAGCUCCCAAGAGGAAGAUUCAGGCCAGAGUCUUCCCACUGCCCAUGUUCGCCCUUCCCACCCAUUGAAGAGCUUCGCCGUGCCAGCAAUCCCGCCUCCAGGACCUCCCACCUAUGAUCCUGCAUUGCCAAGCACACCAUUACUGUCCCAGCAAGCUCUGAACCAUCACAUUCACUCAGUGAAGACAGCCUCCAUCGGGACUCUAGGAAGGAGCCGGCCUCCUAUGCCAGUGGUUGUUCCCAGUGCCCCUGAAGUGCAGGAGACCACAAGGAUGUUGGAAGACUCCGAGAGUAGCUAUGAACCAGAUGAGCUGACCAAAGAGAUGGCCCACCUGGAAGGACUAAUGAAGGACCUAAACGCUAUCACAACAGCAUGACGACCUUCACCAGGACCUGACUUCAAACCUGAGUCUGGAAGUCUUGGAACUUACCCUUGAAAACAAGGAAUUGUACAGAGUACGAGAGGACAGCACUUGAGAACACAGAAUGAGCCAGCAGACUGGCCAGCGCCUCUGUGUAGGGCUGGCUCCAGGCAUGGCCACCUGCCUUCCCCUGGUCAGCCUGGAAGAAGCCUGUGUCGAGGCAGCUUCCCUUUGCCUGCUGAUAUUCUGCAGGACUGGGCACCAUGGGCCAAAAUUUUGUGUCCAGGGAAGAGGCGAGAAGUGCAACCUGCAUUUCACUUUGUGGUCAGGCCGUGUCUUUGUGCUGUGACUGCAUCACCUUUAUGGAGUGUAGACAUUGGCAUUUAUGUACAAUUUUAUUUGUGUCUUAUUUUAUUUUACCUUCAAAAACAAAAACGCCAUCCAAAACCAAGGAAGUCCUUGGUGUUCUCCACAAGUGGUUGACAUUUGACUGCUUGUUCCAAUUAUGUAUGGAAAGUCUUUGACAGUGUGGGUCGUUCCUGGGGUUGGCUUGUUUUUUGGUUUCAUUUUUAUUUUUUAAUUCUGAGUCAUUGCAUCCUCUACCAGCUGUUAAUCCAUCACUCUGAGGGGGAGGAAAUGUUGCAUUGCUGUUUGUAAGCUUUUUUUAUUAUUUUUUUAUUAUAAUUAUUAAAGGCCUGACUCUUUCCUCUCAUCACUGUGAGAUUACAGAUCUAUUUGAAUUGAAUGAAAUGUAACAUUGAAAAGACUUGUUUGUUGCUUUCUGUGCAGUUUCAGUAUUGGGGCGGGUGGGGGGCUGGGGGUUGGUAAUAGGAAAUGGAGGGGCUGCUGAGGUCCUGUGAAUGUUUCUGUCAUUGUACUUUCUUCCAGAAGCCUGCAGAGAAUGGAAGCAUCUUCUUUAUUGUCCUUUCCUGGCAUGUCCAUCCUUAUUGUCACUACGUUGCAACUGGAGUUUGAUUUGGAUCUGGUUUUAAAAUUCUUCUGUGCAAUAGAUGGGUUUGAGGAUUUAGCGGCCCUGAUGUCUUGGUCAUAGCCUGGUAAGAAUGUCCAUGCUGAGGAGCCAGAUGUUGUAUUUCUAACUGCCUGAGUCACACAGAAUAGGGUAAGAGCCUGACCCCAUUCUGUAAAUCAGAAAGCAAGGAUGGAGACCCUUUCCUGCUGCUAUUAUUGGCUCUCUUUGAGGAAGUUGGAGGUUAAGGAAGGAACUUGUUUGUUUCCGUAUACGACUCCUUCUUCUCUCUAGUUCAGUCUUCAGCCAGUCCAGCGCUCUCUUCCACACUUCAGAGCCCCUUCAGAGAAAGCAUUAGCAGGAAUGAGACAAGGCAGAGCUGCAGUGCCCCCUGAGGCUUCCACACAUCUUUCUGAAUAUUAUUUUUCAAGUAACAAGGGCAGGGACAGCGGAAACAGCUGCCCACCCCCCCCAUCCCAGCAGCUCAGCUAAGCCCUGAUGAGAAUGAAGCCACAGGAGUUGUCUGAGGUGAACCCAGCCGCUCAGCCACACAUGGAAGCCAUUGCCUUUGCACAUAGUUCUUGGGUUCUUUUUCCUAAAAAGGUAAGGAGCUGAGGUGUGUGGUUUUUUAAUAUUAAGAAUAUAUAAUGGAAAACACACGACUGACGCUCAGGCAUCUUCCCCUACUCCCCAACAGAUCCCCAGAAGACAGCGUGGAAGGCAGUGUAGACAGUAAAUCGGGCUUCAGUUCUAUAGCCAAGAAGAGAUCAGCUGCUGAAACCACCAGUGGGUACCCCAGGCCACCUGCCUUUGAACUUGGGGAUUUGCCAUGUUUGAUCUUGUCACAUACUUGCUUUUUUACAAGAUGAACUCUUUGUAUUUAUGAUUUGGGGGGCAAUGAAAGGUGCAAUGCAGGAACUGCUGCUGCCGAGCUCGCUGGUCACAUGGGGGUGCCAGGCGGGAUUCUGGAAAACCAGUGCACUUAAACUGAUCCUGAAGAGAGCUGUCCCAGCACUCUGGCCACCAGGAGGGCCAGAUUCCCCAGAAACUACCUUUUGCCCAAAGAACAUGCUCAGUAUUUGGGGCAUUUCCUCCCACAAACCCUGACUGCUUCUGUUACCUCAGGGCCUUGGUACCUGGAUACUGCCACAGAAUUGGGGCGGGUGGGGGAGGGGCCUAUUUUUAAAUAAAAUAACUGUUCAAAGUUGGGGGUUUUUUAAAAAAUUAAGAAAAAGGAAAGCUAUUCUGUAUUGCACCUUUUCACAAUUUAAUACAUUUUCUUACAUUUUCCUGUGAUUUUCGAAACUAAACCAUUGUGUGUCCUGUAGUGUCCUGGUUGAGCUGCCGCUCAGCAGCUUCCUCGGGGGGAUUUGGAACACCUGUGUCUGUCGCCGCACUGCCUGUGGGAGGGGCCCAGAGGGCUGCUGGGACUGGCGUCUGUACACACUUGUUUGGCCUUUUCUGUAGUUGAUGCUGUAAACUCUAUGGCUUUUUAAAAACGAUUUCAUGUUUUUAUUUAGUAUUGGAAAUCCAAUACACUUUUUUAAUCCAAUCAAAC